AAUGACAGGCGUAAAAGAAAACCAUAUUCAGGACAUUCCCUUUCUUGAGCAAAACUGCAAUUUGCAAAAUCAUCGGUGACAGGUAAUGGUGACUGGUGAUUCAUUCCUGGUGAUGUCUUGGGCCAAAUUCCAGAAUCCAAUGUAUAUUCAGAAGGGGCAGGGAGAAGAUCUGCAUGUAUGACUUCACCCAGAAGCCCUGGCAUAUAAACAAGAGGUGAGUUGUCAGUUUCACCCAAUUCCAGGCCUAGCACUUUCCAAACAGACUGAGACCAUGGCAGUCUUCCAUGACAUGCUGCUGCAGCCACUGGGGAUGUUUCUGUGCCUCAGUCUGCAGCUUUCUUCUGCCACCUUUAUAAGGUACAGUAGCACCUGCUUCACCUUUGAUGAAUACUACACCAUAACCCUAGACAUCAAGGCCAGUUCACAUAUCUACGAAAGCAAUGCAGUCUAUUCUGUAUUUGUUCCCGUGAAUGACAGCGUCUAUGCUGUGGUCAUGAAAACCUUGGACGAGAACAGUGACUCAGCGGGCCUCUGGCAAAGAGCGGAUAAAAAUUGCUACAGCAACUCCACGUAUUACGUGAAAGAUCAAUACAUGACGGUCUUAGAGGCACAGUGGCAAGCUCCUGAACCUGAGAACAUAACUGAAGUGGAGAUACAAGCUUUCACUGUCCAGAUCAGAGCGCUGCCUAUACUUUCUACUCUGAAGCUAAGAGAAAAACUGUCAACCUUAGCCUUAGCUGCCAAGAUUCCCCAGAGCUCAGCCUUCAAGCCUUUCUUCAUGAUUACACCCAAGAGUAUCAGACUCGAAGGCUUGGCCAACCAAGUCUUCAGCAGCCCCAUCACAGAGGCCAUUUAUAUCCUGCUUGCUUUUCUCACCAGCACACUUCUCUUCUAAAGGGAAGCCAGGGAAACAAUUGUUUCUGCCUCCACUGCAUCCUCCUACAUUCAGUUCCAAGCUAGUGCUGGGAACCGAAUGUGUGUAAAUGAAGGCUUUACAUUCUCAAAUGUGCAACUUUGCUGCCACGGCUUCAGACCAAAACAAAGAUCUGGAGGCACUCAUUGGCAGGCUUGGGUCACAUAGAUGUUCAUCUGGAUCUUUCAGGACACAUAUUACACUUUUUGAAAAUAUUUAGAACUGGCCGGAACUUAGUCACCUAGGUUCUCCCUAUUGGUUGAACAGGUUGGCAGCCAAUUCCACAGCCAAUCUCAACUUUUGUUCACUGCCAAAUGAUUCCCCUGCAACCUCUGAGUUUCUGUGGGAAGAAUCCUUCCUUACUUUCAAGAUGAUCUCAGAUUUCUAACCAAACCCAUUCAGGUUACAAGGAACUUCUGUGACUCAUGUGACUCAAGAAAGAAAGGAGAAAGGAGAAAUAGCUCUGAGGCUGCUGGCAGCUUCCCAUUUGUCCACACCAGUAGAUUUUGAAGGGCAAGAGAACAGGAACGAACCAUGUCUGAGAAGCCAAUAUAGAAAAAAACUAUGUUAUAAAAACAUUUUUGUCACAACAAAUAAAUUAUACUUUAAACAAGAAUAAUGAAUGUGU